CUCUGACUUCGGGCUUGUUCGCUGGUGGCGUCGGAGCCGAGCCGGACUGGUCAGGAUGAUCACGGACGUGCAGCUCGCCAUCUUCGCCAACAUGCUGGGCGUGUCGCUCUUCUUGCUUGUCGUUCUCUAUCACUACGUGGCCGUCAACAAUCCCAAGAAGCAGGAAUGAAAGUGGCGCUUUCUCCGCCCCAGGGUUCCAGGACAUAGUCUGAGGCAAGAUGGAGGGUAUGAGGGGCCUUCACACUUCACUUCAUCCCUUCUACCCAUCACAACAUACAAAGCAACUACACCUGGAUUUUUCCAAACAACUUUUAUUUCCUCAGAGUCUUCCUUAAUCCUAUGGAACAAGAAGCUGCCACUGAAUAGGGCCCAGUAUAGGGGCUUGCUUUUCUACUCCCUCCCCCCAAUAUAAAAAUAUAGACUUUUUUUUGUGGUCCCAAAA